CCCUUUUGGCUCUCUGACCAGCACCAUGGCGGUUGGCAAGAACAAGCGCCUUACGAAAGGCGGCAAAAAGGGAGCCAAGAAGAAAGUGGUUGAUCCAUUUUCUAAGAAAGAUUGGUAUGAUGUGAAAGCACCUGCUAUGUUCAAUAUAAGAAAUAUUGGAAAGACGCUCGUCACCAGGACCCAAGGAACCAACAAUGAUUGAAGCUCACGUUGAUGUCAAGACUACCGAUGGUUACUUGCUUCGUCUGUUCUGUGUUGGUUUUACUAAAAAACGCAACAAUCAGAUACGGAAGACCUCUUAUGCUCAGCACCAACAGGUCCGCCAAAUCCGGAAGAAGAUGAUGGAAAUCAUGACCCGAGAGGUGCAGACAAAUGACUUGAAAGAAGUGGUCAAUAAAUUGUAAGUGUUUCUUUGCUUCCUCACACAACACAACCUUGAGUAUUGGAUUAUUCCUGAGAUGAGAGAACGCAUAUGAGACAAGGUAAAGGUCUGUUGAAAUCCUGUCUGUGAAUCCUUCUAGCUAUAUCUCUUUAAGUGAAAGAGUGUUAAGUACUCAGUAAAUAUGAUUAUUAUUACUAUUAUUAUUUGAGUCAGAGUCUUGCUCUGUUGCCCAGGCUCGAGUGCAGUAUUGUGAUCCUCCUUGGCUCACUGUAACCACUGCUUCCUGGGUUCAAGCAGUUCUUGAGCCUCAGCCUCCUGAGUAUCUGGGAAUACAGGGGACUGCCACCAUACCCAGCUAAUUUUUUUAAAUUUUUAGUAGAGAUGGGGUUUCAUCAUGUUGGCCAGGCUGGUCUUGAACUCCUGACUUCAGGUGAUCUGCCAGUACUCUAAAUGAUAACAGUUUUUUCGUGUUUAUUUAUUUUGAAUGAAGCUGUCUCACAGUAGAUGGAGUUGAAGGACAGGAAAUGUUUUUCCCCUACUUGGAAAAUACACUGAAUAAGUUGAGUGGGGUGGGAUGUGCCUGGAGUCCCAGCUACUCAGGAGGCUGAGGUGGUAGGAUUGUUUGAGCCCAGGAGUUUGAGGCCAGCCUGGGCAAUAUAGGGAGACCCUGUCCCAAAAAAUAAAAAAUAUACGUAUAUAUAUAUACACACACAAAGAAAAAAUACACUGAAUAGACAAAACCUUUCAUGAUUAAUGAUGCACGGGAAUAAGUGAUGAAAAAAGUUUCGGUCCCAGAUGAUGGCCAGUGAUAACAACAUUUUUCUGAUGUUCCCAUGCAAUAUACAGUUAGCUAAGAGGGUGUAAUGGAAAAAGCAUAAGGCUUGGACUCAGAAGACUCUACUAACUUUGCCACUAGCUAGCUAUGUAAUUCAGAUCAUCUAUCCUUUACAUGUGAAAGGUAAAUAAUGGCUUAUCUUAACAGGAGGAUUUAUGCAGGUUAAAUGAGGUAGGUGUUAUGUGUAGGUUUAUUCCAAGGCUUCUCUACUUUUAAAGGAAAUGGCUUAUAUCUGAGAACUAGGACUUUUAGAAAAAAAUUUACUGUUACUGGUUUGCAGGAUUCCAGACAGCAUUGGAAAA